AGUCAUGUGACCGGCAAUGGCGGCGCUGACGAGAGGUAGGUGAGCCCGGCGCCCCCCACACCCACCGCGCGCCCCCCGGGCCCCGCUCGCACCCCUCACGCGCCCCCCGCUCCCCCGGCGCCCCCUCCUCCACCUCCCCUCCCCGCGCGCGGCUCCGGGCUCCCCGCUCCGUGCCCGGCCGAUCAUCUUUCUAGCACCCUCCAGCCUUGGCCUCCAUUCGGGGGUUCUGAGGGCUGCGAUCGGGCCGACAUGCACCCCCACCCGGCGGUGGGGAUCCGGGGGCUUUGGCUACUGAGGGAUGUGGGGAGUUGGUUCCGGGUCGGGUCUUGGAGGAGGCCGUGGGGGGAGGGCGGGAGCUGCUUCAGUGGAUGCCCCCAGGGACCCUUGCCCAUCCGGGCUGUGCCUCCCUCUGGCCUCUGUCUGGAGGGAGAGACUGGUUCCUUGUCCGGCCUGGGUUGCCACAGAGGAAUCACAGACCCACCCUAAACUGGGGCCCCGCCUCCCUUUUCUGUGCCAGCAGGACUUGGACCUAGGACACCUAGGUCCUGGGUCCCCCGUGAUGGGGAGAGAAGUGUUGCAUCGCGGAUAGACUGUAUGGGCUGAGACUCUAGGGUUCCAUUUUCACUUAUGAAUCUCGAGGUGCAUCUGGCCUUGGGGGACGAUGAUGGAGGCAUGAAGGGACAGCUGCUCCUUCUUGGAUCAGUCAAUAAAUGGAGGUCACACUAAUGGCCCUUCUUUCUGUUUGAGCUGCAUUUGGAAGUGUUGUGGAGACAGCCCCGUAGCCCAAUGCGACCAGACUCAGGGAAAACAUCAGGCCCCUCCAGCUGAGCCCUUGUGUGAGCCCCGCCCCUCCCUAAAUGCCAGACUUGGGAGCUGACAGACAGCACUGCCUGUGCUGGGUUUAAAAGGUGACAAUGAGAACUUUGUUAUUGCAGGGGCUGCUGCCACUUUGUUCACAUCCUUAACAGACUUCAGCAGAAGGGACUGAGUUAGCUCUCAAGGAAGGCUCCCUGGCAAUAGGGGCUGAAUUAUUUGGCAAUGUGGAGCAGGCGAGGAGUUGGGGAGCAUAGGAAAUAUUCCGGUCCAUGUGAUCUGAGGGAGGUGGCAAGAAGACCUCCACCUGUGUGGGCGUUUUCUUUCCUGACUUCUCUUAUGUGUGCCCUAGGCUUUCUUGGGGGCCUCAGAGCUGGGGAAGAAAGGAGGAAGGUUAGCAUGUUGAAGUUCCUUCUUGAGCAACUUGGGGAGAAGCUGAUAAUGGAAUUCUGCAGAGAAGAGAGGAGAUGGAAGGGGAGUUUUUAUUUCUGGGUUGGCUGAGGGGAAUGGUAACAUUUGCCAUCAUAACUUUUUACCCUUCCCCCACUCCCAGUCCUGGUCAGCUGAGUGGAAAUAGAAGGAUUUCUGCUGCCAUCAUCUUCCAUGGGCUUUCCAGGUCACACGACCUACAAGUAGGGAGCAGGGAAAGAAGAGUGAGCCUGCAUGCCAAUUCUAAGCUCUUCAGGAUCAAAAAUGGCAGCCUGUGGAGGCACCUGCAAGAACAAAGUGACUGUGUCCAAGCCCGUGUGGGACUUCCUGAGCAAAGAGACCCCAGCCCGGCUGGCCCGGCUUCGGGAGGAGCACCGUGUGUCCAUCCUCAUAGAUGGCGAGACUUCUGACAUCUAUGUUCUCCAGCUUUCCCCACAGGGUCCUCCCCCGGCCCCUCCAAAUGGGCUCUACCUAGCCCGGAAGGCUCUCAAGGGGCUGCUAAAAGAGGCAGAGAAAGAGCUGAAGAAAGCUCAGAGGCAGGGGGAGCUGAUGGGCUGCCUGGCUCUGGGGGGUGGAGGGGAGCACCCUGAGAUGCACCGCGCAGGCCCACCCCCUCUCCGAGCAGCCCCACUUCUGCCCCCAGGAGCUCGGGGGCUCCCCCCUCCUCCUCCCCCCCUGCCCCCACCUCUUCCUCCUCGCCUUCGGGAGGAGGCAGAAGAGCAGGAGAGCACCUGCCCCAUCUGUCUGGGGGAGAUCCAGAAUGCCAAGACAUUGGAGAAGUGCCGGCAUUCAUUCUGCGAGGGCUGCAUCACCCGGGCUCUGCAGGUGAAAAAGGCCUGCCCCAUGUGCGGCCGCUUCUAUGGGCAGCUGGUGGGCAACCAGCCCCAGAAUGGGCGGAUGCUGGUCUCUAAGGACGCCACCCUCCUACUGCCCAGCUAUGAGAAGUACGGCACCAUUGUCAUCCAGUACGUCUUCCCGCCCGGUGUCCAGGGGGCUGAACACCCAAACCCAGGAGUUCGGUAUCCUGGCACCACACGGGUGGCCUACCUCCCGGACUGCCCUGAGGGCAACAAGGUGCUGACCCUGUUCCGCAAGGCGUUUGACCAGCGUCUCACCUUCACUAUCGGCACGUCCAUGACCACAGGGAGACCGAAUGUCAUCACCUGGAACGACAUCCACCACAAGACCAGCUGCACAGGGGGACCCCAGCUGUUUGGGUACCCAGACCCCACCUACCUGACCCGGGUGCAAGAGGAGCUGAGAGCGAAGGGUAUCACAGAUGACUGAAGGACAUCGCCUUUGCCAAGGCCCCUGCUGUCUGCCUCUACUAGGACCCAGCAGAAGCCUCUUUCUCCUCUCUGCCCCCUGCCCCCCACACCACACCUGUAGGGGACCUGUCUGACUGGGAAGGGAGUUCCGAGAGGGAGGGGGCAAUCCCUUCCCCCAUCCCCCACUGGCCAAGUGUUUCAAUGCAGUGUGAGCCACUCCCUUCUGGCAGAGGCCGACCUCCAAGGCUCUGUUCUCCCCUCCCCGUGUACAUAUACUCCCGGUUUCCCUGCCCCUCCAUUGCCCUUGGCUUUUUCUGGUAUGUGCUGUGCUCCACGACCAAGCCGAGAAAGGACCUAGGGUGGGGAAGGGAGGGUCUCUUGAUUCCUAACCGCCCCCACAUACUGCUCCACCGCUGAACUUCGGGUGCCGGGGAGGAGAAAUUGGGCUGAUGUGAGCUCCCCGUCACCCGCCAUGGAGCCGGCUGUGUGUGUUCAUCAGAUACAGUUCUCCCUUAACCUUGUCCUUUCUCUCCUGUGUCUCAGUCUCCGUCAGUCUGUCUUUCUCCGCUCUUCUCUGACCCCUGUGAGGAACCUCCUUACCCUGUUCUGGAAUCGCUGCCAGACUGUAGCUUUUAAUUUAAUAAAAAUAAAGUAAAAUAUGCAACUCUU